GCUUGCCUGCAAACCUUUACUUCUGAAAUGACUUCCACGGCUGGGACGGGAACCUUCCACCCACAGCUAUGCCUCUGAUUGGUGAAUGGUGAAGGUGCCUGUCUAACUUUUCUGUAAAAAGAACCAGCUGCCUCCAGGCAGCCAGCCCUCAAGCAUCACUUACAGGACCAGAGGUGAGCAUGGGGGAUUCUUGGUUACUUUUUUUUGAAGGACUAGACCUCUGCUUUAUUUGUGAAAAGGGGUCAAGGUGGGGACAGCAGAAGUCAAUUUUUUUGAGUGUUGAUGUAGGGACAAGACAUGACUGUGAUGAGGAGCUGCUUUCGCCAAUUUAACACCAAGAAGAAUUGAGGCUGCUUGGGAGGAAGGCCAGGAGGAACACGAGACUGAGAGAUGAAUUUUCAACAGAGGCUGCAAAGCCUGUGGACUUUAGCCAGCAGACCCUUCUGCCCUCCUUUGCUGGCGACAGCCUCUCAAAUGCAGAUGGUUGUGCUCCCUUGCCUGGGUUUUACCCUGCUUCUCUGGAGCCAGGUAUCAGGGGCCCAGGGCCAAGAAUUCCACUUUGGGCCCUGCCAAGUGAAGGGGGUUGUUCCCCAGAAACUGUGGGAAGCCUUCUGGGCUGUGAAAGACACUAUGCAAGCUCAGGAUAACAUCACGAGUGCCCGGCUGCUGCAGCAGGAGGUUCUGCAGAACGUCUCGGAUGCUGAGAGCUGUUACCUUGUCCACACCCUGCUGGAGUUCUACUUGAAAACUGUUUUCAAAAACUACCACAAUAGAACAGUUGAAGUCAGGACUCUGAAGUCAUUCUCUACUCUGGCCAACAACUUUGUUCUCAUCGUGUCACAACUGCAACCCAGUCAAGAAAAUGAGAUGUUUUCCAUCAGAGACAGUGCACACAGGCGGUUUCUGCUAUUCCGGAGAGCAUUCAAACAGUUGGACGUAGAAGCAGCUCUGACCAAAGCCCUUGGGGAAGUGGACAUUCUUCUGACCUGGAUGCAGAAAUUCUACAAGCUCUGAAUGUCUAGACCAGGACCUCCCUCCCCCUGGCACUGGUUUGUUCCCUGUGUCAUUUCAAACAGUCUCCCUUCCUAUGCUGUUCACUGGACACUUCACGCCCUUGGCCAUGGGUCCCAUUCUUGGCCCAGGAUUAUUGUCAAAGAAGUCAUUCUUUAAGCAGCGCCAGUGACAGUCAGGGAAGGUGCCUCUGGAUGCUGUGAAGAGUCUACAGAGAAGAUUCUUGUAUUUAUUACAACUCUAUUUAAUUAAUGUCAGUAUUUCAACUGAAGUUCUAUUUAUUUGUGAGACUGUAAGUUACAUGAAGGCAGCAGAAUAUUGUGCCCCAUGCUUCUUUACCCCUCACAAUCCUUGCCACAGUGUGGGGCAGUGGAUGGGUGCUUAGUAAGUACUUAAUAAACUGUGGUGCUUUUUUUGGCCUGUCUUUGGAUUGUUAAAAAACAGAGAGGGAUGCUUGGAUGUAAAACUGAACUUCAGAGCAUGAAAAUCACACUGUCUUCUGAUAUCUGCAGGGACAGAGCAUUGGGGUGGGGGUAAGGUGCAUCUGUUUGAAAAGUAAACGAUAAAAUGUGGAUUAAAGUGCCCAGCACAAAGCAGAUCCUCAAUAAACAUUUCAUUUCCCACCCACACUCGCCAGCUCACCCCAUCAUCCCUUUCCCUUGGUGCCCUCCUUUUUUUUUUAUCCUAGUCAUUCUUCCCUAAUCUUCCACUUGAGUGUCAAGCUGACCUUGCUGAUGGUGACAUUGCACCUGGAUGUACUAUCCAAUCUGUGAUGACAUUCCCUGCUAAUAAAAGACAACAUAACUCAAGUCUGGCAGACUUUCUUCUCUAUUUCUGGAUGAAUGCCCAGUGAGACUGUGUUGUACAGCUAGAAAAGGCCUUCUUCCCAAUAGCAAGGCUGUGCAUCUAGCCUCAAGCUCUGGCUGAACUUUGUGGUCGACAUCAAUCUAAAGAUACAGUGUCUGACUAUAACCUUGUUCCAAAAACCUAGGCAAAGAGUAUAUGUAGGAGGUGGGAUAUCACUUCCAUGACAUAAGUGCUAUUGCAGAGCCGUGGCCACCCAGGAACUCCUGACUGCUUUCC